CUUCGCUUUUCUAACCACGAACAGUGCUCGUUCGUUCGCAGGGCCAGCAAGGAGAGCCCCGCCCCCGCCCGCCGCCCGCCGCCCGCCGCCCGCCGCCUUUGGAUCCCGCGGACUCCGCCCGGCCCGGCCUCCCCAGGCAUGGCGCCGCUGCGCUUCUCCGCCAAUCUGUCCUGGCUAUUCCCCGAGCUCUCCGGCCUCCCCGCGCGGGUGCGGGCCGCGGGCAGCUCGGGCUUCGAGGCCGUCGAGGUGGCCUGGCCGUACGCGGAGACGCCUGAGGCGCUGGCGCGCGCCGCGCGAGAAGCGGGGCUGCGGCUUGUACUGAUCAACACGCCCCCGGGAGACCAAGAGAAGGGGGAAAUGGGGCUGGGGGCCGUCCCCGGGAGACAGGCGGCCUUCCGAGAGGGACUGGAGCAGGCCGUGCGGAGUGGGCAUUGCUUGAUGGGCAGGAAGUUGAGUGUUCCUUGCAAGGGUGCUGUGGCAAGAGGAGGCCUGGUGUAUUUGGCAGCGUUCCUGAGGCUGGACAUGAUCCACCUGAUGGCUGGCCGAGUACCCCAGGGAGCUGAUCGAAUAGCAGUCAAGGCUGAGAUGGAGGCCGUUUUUCUGGAGAACCUGAGGCAUGCAGCUGGGGUUUUGGCUCAGGAGGACCUCGUGGGACUGCUGGAGCCCAUCAACACCCGCAUCACUGACCCCCAGUACUUCCUGGACACGCCCCAGCAGGCGGCAGCCAUCUUACAGAAGGUAGGAAGACCCAACCUCCAAUUACAAAUGGACAUAUUCCACUGGCAGAUCAUGGAUGGGAACCUGACAGGAAACAUCCGGGAGUUCCUGCCCAUUGUUGGGCAUGUGCAGGUGGCACAGGUCCCAGGCCGAGGGGAGCCCAGCAGCCCCGGAGAGCUGAAUUUCCCCUAUCUGUUUCAACUGCUGGAAGAUGAAGGCUACAAAGGCUUCGUGGGCUCCAGUGCCAGGGUUGCUGUGAAGAUGGGAGAGCUUCUGAACCCACCUCAUUAAAGGAUGAGAAACCCAGGGUCCGAGAGCAAAGGGACUUGACGGUGGCCACAAGUGCUUCAAAGGCAGAGCUGGGAUUGGAACCCAGGUGUCAUCUCGAUGGGAAUGUCCAGCAGUGAUGUCCAAGUGGGAAGUGAAGACCCGAAGGCUCAAGGGACACAGGUGGCUGACAGUGGUCAAAGGCUAGGGGGCAGGAUUCAGGCAGAGGAGCUCUAGGGGGUGUUUGCCACCCUGUGUGAACUCCCGAGACUCUACCAGGGGGGCCGAAAGGAGUACCCCAGAAGGGCCCAAGGGGUCCUCGGGGUUGACCUGACUCUCUGGAGUCCUGGAUGGGUCAGUGGCUGUGGGUGUUUGGGGAGGGCGGUUCCUGCUGCCAGGCUGGGGCAGCAGACCCUCAAGACAUAGUUACAAAGCC